AGAGCCACCCUGAGCUCGGUGAGAGCAAAGCCAGAGCCCCCAGUCCUUUGCUCGCCGGCUUGCUAGCUCUCUCGAUCACUCCCUCCCUUCCUCCCUCCCUUCCUCCCGGCGGCCGCGGCGGCGCUGGGGAAGCGGUGAAGAGGAGUGGCCCGGCCCUGGAAGAAUGCGGCUCUGACAAGGGGACAGAACCCAGCGCAGUCUCCCCACGGUUUAAGCAGCACUAGUGAAGCCCAGGCAACCCAACCGUGCCUGUCUCGGACCCCGCACCCAAACCACUGGAGGUCCUGAUCGAUCUGCCCACCGGAGCCUCCGGGCUUCGACAUGCUGGAGGAGCCCCGGCCGCGGCCUCCGCCCUCGGGCCUCGCGGGUCUCCUGUUCCUGGCGUUGUGCAGUCGGGCUCUAAGCAAUGAGAUUCUGGGCCUGAAGUUGCCUGGCGAGCCGCCGCUGACGGCCAACACCGUGUGCUUGACGCUGUCCGGCCUGAGCAAGCGGCAGCUAGGCCUGUGCCUGCGCAACCCCGACGUGACGGCGUCCGCGCUUCAGGGUCUGCACAUCGCGGUCCACGAGUGUCAGCACCAGCUGCGCGACCAGCGCUGGAACUGCUCCGCGCUUGAGGGCGGCGGCCGCCUGCCGCACCACAGCGCCAUCCUCAAGCGCGGUUUCCGAGAAAGUGCUUUUUCCUUCUCCAUGCUGGCUGCUGGGGUCAUGCACGCAGUAGCCACGGCCUGCAGCCUGGGCAAGCUGGUGAGCUGUGGCUGUGGCUGGAAGGGCAGUGGUGAGCAGGAUCGGCUGAGGGCCAAACUGCUGCAGCUGCAGGCACUGUCCCGAGGCAAGAGUUUCCCCCACUCUCUGCCCAGCCCUGGCCCUGGCUCAAGCCCCAGCCCUGGCCCCCAGGACACAUGGGAAUGGGGUGGCUGUAACCAUGACAUGGACUUUGGAGAGAAGUUCUCUCGGGAUUUCUUGGAUUCCAGGGAAGCUCCCCGGGACAUCCAGGCACGAAUGCGAAUCCACAACAACAGGGUGGGGCGCCAGGUGGUAACUGAAAACCUGAAGCGGAAAUGCAAGUGUCAUGGCACAUCAGGCAGCUGCCAGUUCAAGACAUGCUGGAGGGCGGCCCCAGAGUUCCGGGCAGUGGGGGCGGCGUUGAGGGAGCGGCUGGGCCGGGCCAUCUUCAUUGAUACCCACAACCGCAAUUCUGGAGCCUUCCAGCCCCGUCUGCGUCCCCGUCGCCUCUCAGGAGAGCUGGUCUACUUUGAGAAGUCUCCUGACUUCUGUGAGCGAGACCCCACUAUGGGCUCCCCAGGGACAAGGGGCCGGGCCUGCAACAAGACCAGCCGCCUGUUGGAUGGCUGUGGCAGCCUGUGCUGUGGCCGUGGGCACAACGUGCUCCGGCAGACACGAGUUGAGCGCUGCCAUUGCCGCUUCCACUGGUGCUGCUAUGUGCUGUGUGAUGAGUGCAAGGUUACAGAGUGGGUGAAUGUGUGUAAGUGAGGGUCAGCCUUACCUUGGGGCUGGGGAAGAGGACUGUGUGAGAGGGGCGCCUUUUCAGCCCUUUGCUCUGAUUUCCUUCCAAGGUCACUCUUGGUCCCUGGAAGCUUAAAGUAUCUACCUGGAAACAGCUUUAGGGGUGGUGGGGGUCAGGUGGACUCUGGGAUGUGUAGCCUUCUCCCCAACAAUUGGAGGGUCUUGAGGGGAAGCUGCCACCCCUCUUCUGCUCCUUAGACACCUGAAUGGACUAAGAUGAAAUGCACUGUAUUGCUCCUCCCACUUCUCAACUCCAGAGCCCCUUUAACCCUGAUUCAUACUCCUUUUGGCUGGGGAGUCCCUAUAGUUUCACCACUCCUCUCCCUUGAGGGAUAACCCCAGGCACUGUUUGGAGCCAUAAGAUCUGUAUCUAGAAAGAGAUCACCCACUCCUAUGUACUAUCCCCAAACUCCUUUACUGCAGCCUGGGCUCCCUCUUGUGGGAUAAUGGGAGACAGUGGUAGAGAGGUUUUUCUUGGGAAAGAGACAGAGUGCUGAGGGGCACUCUCCCCUGAAUCCUCAGAGAGUUGUCUGUCCAGGCCCUUAGGGAAGUUGUCUCCUUCCAUUCAGAUGUUAAUGGGGACCCUCCAAAGGAAGGGGUUUUCCCAUGACUCUUGGAGCCUCUUUUUCCUUCUUCAGCAGGAAGGGUGGGAAGGGAUAAUUUAUCAUACUGAGACUUGUUCUUGGUUCCUGUUUGAAACUAAAAUAAAUUAAGUUACUGGA